AGCUCCGAGGGCGGCUGGCCCGGUCGCGGUCGCGGCUCUUUCCAGCUCCUGGCAGCCGGGCACCCGAAGGAACGGGUCGUGCAACGACGCAGCUGGACCUGGCCCAGCCAUGGACCGAAAAGUGGCCCGAGAAUUCCGGCAUAAGGUGGAUUUUCUGAUUGAAAAUGAUGCAGAGAAGGACUAUCUCUAUGAUGUGCUGCGAAUGUACCACCAGACCAUGGACGUGGCCGUGCUCGUGGGAGACCUGAAGCUGGUCAUCAAUGAACCCAGCCGUCUGCCUCUGUUUGAUGCCAUUCGGCCGCUGAUCCCACUGAAGCACCAGGUGGAAUAUGAUCAGCUGACCCCCCGGCGCUCCAGGAAGCUGAAGGAGGUGCGUCUGGACCGUCUGCACCCCGAAGGCCUCGGCCUGAGUGUGCGUGGUGGCCUGGAGUUUGGCUGUGGGCUCUUCAUCUCCCACCUCAUCAAAGGCGGUCAGGCAGACAGCGUCGGGCUCCAGGUAGGGGACGAGAUCGUCCGGAUCAAUGGAUAUUCCAUCUCCUCCUGUACCCAUGAGGAGGUCAUCAACCUCAUUCGAACCAAGAAAACUGUGUCCAUCAAAGUGAGACACAUCGGCCUGAUCCCCGUGAAAAGCUCUCCUGAUGAGCCCCUCACUUGGCAGUAUGUGGAUCAGUUUGUGUCGGAAUCUGGGGGCGUGCGAGGCAGCCUGGGCUCCCCUGGAAAUCGGGAAAACAAGGAGAAGAAGGUCUUCAUCAGCCUGGUAGGCUCCCGAGGCCUUGGCUGCAGCAUUUCCAGCGGCCCCAUCCAGAAGCCUGGCAUCUUUAUCAGCCAUGUGAAACCUGGCUCCCUGUCUGCUGAGGUGGGAUUGGAGAUAGGGGACCAGAUUGUCGAAGUCAAUGGCGUCGACUUCUCUAACCUGGAUCACAAGGAGGCUGUAAAUGUGCUGAAGAGUAGCCGCAGCCUGACCAUCUCCAUUGUAGCUGCAGCUGGCCGGGAGCUGUUCAUGACAGACCGGGAGCGGCUGGCAGAGGCGCGGCAGCGUGAGCUGCAGCGGCAGGAGCUUCUCAUGCAGAAGCGGCUGGCGAUGGAGUCCAACAAGAUCCUCCAGGAGCAGCAGGAGAUGGAGCGGCAAAGGAGAAAAGAAAUUGCCCAGAAGGCAGCAGAGGAAAAUGAGAGAUACCGGAAGGAGAUGGAACAGAUUGUAGAGGAGGAAGAGAAGUUUAAGAAGCAAUGGGAAGAAGACUGGGGCUCAAAGGAACAGCUACUCUUGCCUAAAACCAUCACUGCUGAGGUACACCCAGUACCCCUUCGCAAGCCAAAGUAUGAUCAGGGAGUGGAACCUGAGCUCGAGCCCGCAGAUGACCUGGAUGGAGGCACGGAGGAGCAGGGAGAGCAGAAAGGAAAAGAUAAGAAGAAAGCCAAGUAUGGCAGCCUGCAGGACUUGAGAAAGAAUAAGAAAGAACUGGAGUUUGAGCAAAAGCUUUACAAAGAGAAAGAGGAAAUGCUGGAGAAGGAAAAGCAGCUAAAGAUCAACCGGCUGGCCCAGGAGGUGUCUGAGACAGAGCGGGAAGACCUUGAAGAAUCGGAAAAGAUUCAAUAUUGGGUGGAGAGGCUCUGUCAAACGCGCCUCGAGCAGAUUUCCUCUGCUGAUAAUGAGAUUUCAGAGAUGACCACAGGGCCCCCGCCUCCCCCGCCUUCUGUGUCUCCCCUGGCCCCACCCUUGAGACGCUUCGCAGGCGGACUGCACCUGCACACCACUGACCUGGACGACAUCCCUUUGGACAUGUUCUACUAUCCCCCCAAGACUCCCUCUGCCUUGCCUGUGAUGCCCCACCCUCCACCCUCCAACCCACCCCACAAGGUCCCGGCGCCCCCUGUCCUUCCCUUAUCUGGCCAUGUGAGCGCCUCAUCCUCUCCAUGGGUGCAGCGCACUCCACCCCCCAUUCCCAUCCCUCCCCCGCCAUCCGUUCCCACCCAAGACCUCACUCCCACCCGCCCACUGCCCUCGGCGCUGGAAGAAGCACUGAGCAACCAUCCCUUCCGCACUGGGGACACAGGCAAUCCAGUGGAGGACUGGGAGGCAAAGAACCACAGUGGGAAGCCCACUAACUCCCCUGUCCCUGAACAGAGCUUCCCACCCACCCCAAAGGAAUGCCCCCUCCGUGUGCAUGUGUGGACAUCCUGCAUGUAUAUGGUGGUUCUCACUGAUUUUGAAGUGCUGUAUUGUAUGGUGAAUGGCCUGGGACCUUUGGGGUAAGCAACGGUGUGUCCAUUUGAUAUUCAUUGCUCUCUCUUAGCUCUUCUUUGCUAGUGUAGGCUGGUAACUUUCAAUGUAGGACUUGGAAGUCUAUGUUAAUGAAUAGCCAGCACUCUGUCACAUCCAGUCACUUCCUGAUAUUAUCCCAGAAAGCCUUGAAUAUGGGAAAUGGCUCCUGAUUUAACGGGAAAAAAAGGGAGGGGAGGAGGAAGCAGGGGCGUAUUUGGCUCUGUAAAUGAAGUGAUAACACUGUACCAUCAAAUGCAGUAUUAGGACAUUCCAGUGCCAUUUUCUACAGUACUGGCCAACUGCACUGGCUUGAAGUGUAAUACCCAGAAAUUUCUGGCCAAUUUCCAGCUAUAGAAAAAAUGAAGAUGAGAGAGUUCCUAGAAAUAAUUUACUAUUAAAAGAAUAGGAAUGUUUUUCUUGGAUGUUAGGAAGAUGAACAGUGUCUUUCUGAAAAAGACAUAUUUCUUAUUAAUUAUUCGUAAUCCAAAGACUAUUUUGAAACAUGCAAUCUCUGAGGAAGACAGGGAGCUUGGAUCCCAUGAAGGGAAAAACAAAAUAUUAUUCCACUCCCGUAGCCAUGAGGCCAGGCUUGAGUCAGUGCAAAGGCAUCUCAUGUCAGCUGAGGGUAGCAGGGGUUGCUGAGGGAGGGCAUAGUCAAUAGCACCUGACCAGUGGUUUUUAUUAACCUUCCCUGCAUGGAUUUGAGUUCCUGCGUGGAGAGCAGGACAAGCAUCUCAGAGCACUCAGGAGAGCUUACAAGGAAGGUGGGAGUGAAGAAAGUGCCAGAUGCCAGCAAGGCUGAAGCUUCCAGCGGGAGACUCUCAGAGGGACCCUUUCUGGACCUCUGGUUGGGGUCGUGAGCCCUGCAGCUUUGACAGGAAGAAAUCUGCCUGUUCUCGGGACAUCUUUCCCCAGAGCCCAGCCAGGAGCUGGUUUCUAGAGCUGAGUUAGCCUUGCACAACAUUUUUCUCUGUAAGUGGCCUCCAUCAAGAUGAGCAGUAGCUUUUCCUCAACAAAUUUGAUUCCACUUUGAUUGAGUACCUGCCUGGGGCCUCUCUCUGUGAAGGGGAGAGGGGAGCAGUGCUGAAGAGGAUGCAGAGGAGAUUGACAUGCCUGUGCUUUCCAGGACUUUGCCAUCUGAAGGAUGAGCUGCUGCCCAGGCAGGCUUCUGCUAUAAAAUAUGCAUAAGCCAUGCGCUAUGGGAGGGAUUCAUUCUAACUGAAGAUUGAAGACACCUCUGUAGAGUAGAGGGCUUACGAGCUGAGCCUUGAGGGAUGGCAACACAUGGAGGAUGGGAGCAAGGGCAUUGCAAGUGCAGGGAACAUAAAGAUGGCAAGUUGGAGUAGCAGGGAGUUGGCCUGCCUGGGUUUGAAUCCUGGCUGUGCCACUUACUAGCUAGGUAACUGAACACAUGCUACUUCAUCUAUCUGAGCCUGGGCAUCCCUGUCCAAAAAUAGGAAUGCUAAUGGCAGCUACCUAUUCGAAUCAAAUAAGUUAAUACAUGGACACAUUCUAAGUUAAGAAUGGCAAGAGUGGCAGGCACAUCGUGGAUGUUCAGUAGACAUUAACUAUGGUUAUUGAUAGUCCAGAGUAAAAGAAAAUUUGGGUGAAGCUGCAAACCUGGGAUCUUAGCAAUCUCAGUGUCAGCAAAACUUUGAGUCAGGAUCAAGAUUCAAGACAGAGUCCAGACUUCUCAGAUUCUUCAAGGCAUCACCAAGUUCCCACUGUUAGUUCCUGAUCAGAGCCCAGGGAAGGUUAAAAGCCCCCCAACACAAGGAGCCUCUGAAGAACUGGACUAUAAAUGUCACAAGCGACAUCAAAGCCAGGGUUGUCCCAGCCUCAAAAGCCAGGGGGCUGUUGCUUGGUUGGCUUCAUUUGGCCCACCUCUCACCCUUGUACCACCCACCCUCCUCCUCCCUGCAUGCCCCUGGCAAGCUGUCAUCAGUGCUGCAGCAGGAAGUGUGAGUGACCACACGCCCACACAGUCAGCCCAGCCACCAGCAGGCCCCAAGUCAUGGAAACAAACACCUGUGUUGGCUUGACACUUGUGCCUGCCACACCAGCACCGGCCAUAGGGGGGUUUUCAGGGCCAGAUCUAUCCACAGGCACUGUCCCAUGUUCUCACCAUACUAUUUAGUCAUUCAUUUAUUCAUUCAACACAUGCUUAUUGAGCACCUACUAUAUGCCAAGGCACUAUGCAGGGCACUGGGAAUCCCUGCUGGAUAGACAGCUGCAGUCUCCCUUCUCAAGACAGUCUGGUGGGGAACAAAGAAAAGUAGGCACCCGCCACACCAUCAGCGUGGAGACGGAGGAAGCACAGGUGCUAUAAUAAGGAAGAGGGCUGGAGUAGAGGAAAAGCUCAAGGGAGGCUUCCAGAAGGCAGUGACGCCCAACUUAAGACCUAGGAGGCAAAGCGGAAGAAGGAAGAGCACGUGCAAAGGCCUCAAGGCAAGAAAGCCUGGCAUUUUUUGAGGCUAAAGCUAGGCAGUGUGAGGAGCGUGGCGAGGAGUGAGAGAUAAGGCUGAAAAGGAAGCUAGAGAAGCUCAUGAAAGGCCUUGGGAGUCAAGCCAAUGAGCUCAGUAGUCAAUGCGGACACUGGGGAGGGUUUGGGGGCAGGGCUGUGAACUGAUUUGAUACAUCUUGCCCAAAAAGAUCAAGUGGGUUAGAGCCAAGCAGACAGGUUGCGUCAGCUCCCCUGGAUGCCUCUCUUACUGGUCUUCACCCCAUGGCCCCUAGAGACUAUGUGCCUACCAACUAGGAACAGCAGAUGCUUCACACUGUGGUCCAGGGACUGGAACUGUGGCCAAAGAGACAGCCCUUAAAGACAAGGGACACUGGAUAGCACCCAUGGCCACUGAGAGAAGGGUCUGAAAGUGUGUCUCCUGGGUGACACUGGCUGCUGGCACCCCCAAGCCAGGCUCUAGCUCAAGCGUCCAAUUUCUUAGAGCCGCUCAGUAGUUUCUGUGAUCUCAGCCCACACUGUGGCCAAUGGGCUUCUCAUCUCUCUGCUGAGGAUCACAACCCCAGGACCUCGAGCAGUUGAAUGACCAGGCUGGCUUCACAUAUGCAUGGGUGUAGAUUUGCAUGUGUGUAGAAGUAGCAUGGCUGGCCUUGGCCACCCCACCAUGACCUCACCUGGGUCCCUGUUAAACUAACUCCUUAGACAUUUUGCCCAAGCCCACAGCCUCCACGAGGCCCUGGCGUGUCCACCAUCUCCAAACCUGUCAUGGUCCACCAGGAGCCCAAUUUCAUCUACAGGCCAGCUGUGAAAUCUGAAGUUCUGGUAAGCCCCUUGGGUCCCCUCCAGGUUGUCUCUAGAGGAGCAGACCAGGGCUACCUCCCCUGGGCUCUGCUGUCUCUGGAGGGCAAGUGAGGUGGGACAAAAAUGCAGAUCACAGAUGCCAUCUCUUAACCUUCUUAUUGGCCAAGAGAUGAGGCCACAUGGGUGUAAGUGGAUGUUGACAUGACCAGUGGAAUUUCUGUUCCCCACUUGACUGAACAGCCUGGAGCUCUGUCUAAAAGUAAUAAUGAUCGCUACGACCUGUGAAGAGCCUACUAUAUACCAGGCUCUGCAUGGCCUCAAUUAAUCUUCACAGCAGGACUGUGAGAUGGUUCCUGUGGUCAUCCUGUUUAACACUCGAGGAAAGGGAGGUUUAGAGAGGUUACCAGAGGGGCACCAGGUUCCCCAGGCAGAGCCUGGACUUAAUACUUACCCUCAUGCCUUUCAUACUCCAAAGCCCACGCUGUUACCCUCGUUGCCAUCUUGCCAAAACCUACAGAGAUUCCAGGUGCCCUGGCCCCUGCCCUAAGGCCUGUUGUGGCCUGGCAUGAAACACCCUCAGAUGGGAAACUGGCCAGAGCAGGUUCACUCCCUUUCUCCAACUUACUUCUCACCUCUCACUGUGACUGGAAGUCUGAGGUGUGGUCCUGGGGAAGUGAGAAAUGUCCGCCAGUCUCAGUUACUGACGGCUAAGGGAGCUGGGAUUCGUGUGCACCUCCCAGAGGUGCCGACCACUGGCUGGCCUCCCAUGCACAGUGAGAAGACAGUCAUGUCAGAAUUUUAACUUCCCUUUCAAGGAAACUCUAUCCAAAUGUCAGGGCAGGACAGCUGAGAUAUUUAUUUUGGGCCUUAACUGUCCCGUCAGCUCCCCAGAGAGCAAAGUUUUUGCUCCUGGGACAGCCUGCGGAUGCAUCCAUGUCAUGUUCUCUGGCUAAUAUCAAGGGGUGGUGUCUGCUUGACAACAACUGGGUAGCAUCUUUGGGCAUUGAGCAGGCCUUUAACGUAAGCCAGACUGCUCGGGGAGGGACAUUGGCACGGCAGCCCCAGACUGGCAGGCCCGAAGCCUGGCACCAGGGGGCAGCCAAGACCUAUUGGUAACAUCCAAUGUGGAACUUUUUUUUUUUUCCUCUGGCAGCCACAGGAGAUGUUGAAGAGGAUGGUGGUUUAUCAGACAGCAUUCAGACAA